AGUCGACCGUGGACCGCGCUGCGAGCCUCGGAGACGCCGUAGAAGGAGACCUGCUUCCGGGACUGGACCAGGCGCCUGCGACUCUUCUCAGACGCCGACGUGCACGAGGUUUGGCUCCCAGGUGUCCUGCCUGCCAGACCCGCGGUAGCUCGGCUCGGCCAGUUUUGCUAGGGCUGCCUGGCGAGCCACACCAAUUCCCAUCCUUUGGUAUCGCCAGGAUUCGGCGGCUGUGAAACUGAUUUCCGGUCGCUAAGGUCUCCAUGGAGACAGCACUUUAACCACUUUCUCCCACUGUCAUUCCUCGACUCCACGUGGUUCAGAAAUCGCCCAGAGAAUGUUUGUGGGAGUCAGCCAGGAAGGUGUAGAGUGAAGCAGCGUUCUAAAGGGAAGCAUGACUACUAUUAAUUCUAUUUAAAAUGGGUGUAAAGAAGAAGAAAGAAAUGCAAGUUGCUGCGCUGACCAUUUGCCAUCAGGACCUUGAAACUUUGAAAUCUUUUGCUGAUGUGGAAGGGAAAAAUCUAGCUUCUUUGCUGUUACAUUGUGUGCAACUCACGGAUGGAGUGUCACAAAUCCAUUAUAUUAAACAGAUUGUGCCUCUGCUGGAGAAAGCAGAUAAAAAUGGCAUGUGUGAUCCCACUAUUCAAAGUUGUUUGGAUAUCUUAGCAGGCAUUUAUCUUUCUUUGAGUCUAAAGAAUCCCUUGAAGAAAGUAUUGGCAAGCUCACUAAAUAGCCUGCCUGAUUUUUUUCUACCUGAGGCUAUGCACCGUUUUACUUCUCGUCUUCAGGAAGAAUUGAAUACUACUGACUUAUACUCUUACAGGAAAGUUACUGACAAUAUUUCUUCCUGUAUGGAGAACUUUAACUUGGGUAGAGCAAGUGUUAAUAAUCUGCUUAAAAAUGUGCUUCAUUUUCUGCAGAAGAGUUUAAUUGAAAUCCUGGAAGAAAAUAGAAAAUGUGCUGGAAAUCAUAUUAUUCAAACACAGUUGAUGAAUGACUUACUGGUAGGCAUUAGAGUUUCAAUGAUGUUAGUACAGAAAGUACAAGAUUUCCAGGGAAAUCUUUGGAAGACUUCCGAUUCUCCCAUAUGGCAAAAUAUGUGUGGAUUGCUGAGUAUUUUUACCAAGGUUUUAAGCGAUGAUGAUCUGUUACAGACUGUACAGAGCACAUCUGGAUUAGCUAUUAUUCUUUUUAUUAAGACUAUGUUUCACCCGUCUGAAAAGAUUCCUCAUUUGAUUAGCAGUGUGCUGCUUCGUUCAGUGGACUGCACCAGUGUCCCCGAGUGGUUUAUGAGCAGCUGCAGGAGCCUCUGUUGUGGUGACAUCUCUCAGUCAGCUGUCUUAUUCCUCUGUCAGGGGACACUUGCCAUGUUGGACUGGCAGAACGGAAGCAUGGGUCGGAGUGGGGAGGCCCUGCUCUUGGAUACUGCACAUGUUUUGUUCACCUUGAGUUCACAGAUUAAAGAGCCAACGCUGGAAAUGUUUCUGUCUAGAAUCUUAGCAUCCUGGACUAAUUCAGCCAUACAAGUCCUUGAAUCAAGUUCCCCGAGCCUAACGGACAGCCUGAAUGGGAAUUCAAGUAUAGUUGGGAGACUUUUGGAAUAUGUCUAUACCCAUUGGGAACAUCCAUUGGAUGCUCUGAGACACCAAACCAAAAUCAUGUUCAAAAACCUUCUCCAAAUGCACCGGCUCACUGUGGAAGGUGCAGAUUUCGUCCCUGAUCCUUUCUUUGUGGAAUUGACUGAGAGUCUUUUACGAUUGGAAUGGCAUAUUAAAGGAAAGUACACGUGCCUUGGUUGUUUGGUAGAGUGCAUAGGAGUUGAACAUAUUUUGGCUAUAGAUAAAACUAUUCCAUCUCAAAUCUUAGAGGUGAUGGGAGACCAGUCAUUGGUACCUUAUGCAAGUGACCUCUUGGAAACCAUGUUUAGAAAUCAUAAGAGUCAUUUGAAAUCCCAGACUGCUGAGAGUUCUUGGAUUGACCAGUGGCAUGAGACUUGGGUUUCUCCUCUCCUUUUUAUAUUGUGUGAAGGAAACUUGGAUCAAAAAUCUUACGUGAUUGAUUAUUACUUGCCAAAAUUAUUAAGUUACAGCCCUGAAAGCUUACAGUACAUGGUAAAGAUUCUUCAGACUUCUAUUGAUGCUAAAACUGGACAAGAGCAAUCUUUCCCAUCCUUAGGGUCUUGUAAUAGCAGGGGGGCUCUGGGAGCUUUGAUGGCAUGUCUGCGAAUAGCUAGAGCUCAUGGACAUCUUCAGUCUGCAACUGAUACCUGGGAGAACCUCGUGUCUGAUGCAAGAAUAAAGCAAGGCUUAAUUCAUCAGCAUUGCCAAGUAAGGAUAGAUACAUUAGGCUUGCUUUGUGAAAGUAAUCGGAGCACAGAAAUUGUUUCCAUGGAAGAAAUGCAGUGGAUUCAGUUCUUUAUUACAUACAAUCUUAACAGCCAGUCUCCAGGAGUGCGGCAACAGAUCUGUUCUCUUCUUAAAAAGUUGUUUUGUAGGAUACAGGAAAGUUCUCAGGUACUUUAUAAAUUGGAGCAGAGUAAAUCCAAACGUGAACCAGAGAAUGAGUUAACCAAACAGCACCCUUCUGUUUCUUUACAGCAGUAUAAGAAUUUCAUGUCAUCCAUUUGUAACAGUCUUUUUGAAGCAUUGUUUCCUGGAUCUUCCUACUCGACUAGAUUUUCAGCUUUAACCAUUUUAGGUUCAAUAGCUGAAGUUUUUCAUGUCCCAGAAGGCAGAAUUUAUACAGUAUAUCAGCUGAGUCAUGAUAUUGAUGUUGGUCGUUUCCAAACACUAAUGGAAUGUUUUACCAGCACUUUUGAAGACGUGAAAAUUUUAGCAUUUGAUCUUCUGAUGAAGUUAUCAAAAACAGCUGUACAUUUUCAGGAUUCGGGGAAACUGCAAGGCUUAUUUCAGGCAGCAUUGGAGCUCAGCACAAGCACCAAACCAUACGACUGUGUGACAGCUUCCUACCUGCUGAACUUCUUAAUCUGGCAGGAUGCUCUACCGUCAUCCUUGUCUGCCUACUUAACUCAGCAAGUUGCAUGUGAUAAUGGAGAUAGGCCUGCUGCUGUGGUGGAAAGGAACACAUUAAUGGUUAUCAAAUGCUUGAUGGAAAAUCUUGAGGAAGAAGUAUCUCAGGCUGAAAAUUCUCUGCUUCAGGCAGCAGCAGCAUUUCCAAUGUAUGGGCGAGUCCACUGUAUAACAGGAGCUUUGCAGAAGUUAUCUCUAAACAGCCUGCAGUUGGUGAGCGAGUGGAGACCUGUGGUAGAGAAGCUCCUUUUGAUGUCCUACAGGCUUUCCACUGUGGUGUCUCCAGUCAUUCAGAGCUCAUCCCCUGAAGGCCUCAUCCCAAUGGACACUGAUUCAGAGUCAGCAAGCCGCUUACAGAUGAUUCUGAAUGAGAUUCAGCCUCGAGAUACUAAUGAUUAUUUUAACCAAGCCAAAAUAUUGAAAGAACAUGAUAGCUUUGAUAUGAAGGACUUGAAUGCUAGUGUGGUGAAUAUUGAUACUUCUACAGAAAUCAAAGGUAAAGAAGUAAAAACAUGUGAUGUAACUGCGCAGAUGGUGCUGGUAUGUUGUUGGAGAAGUAUGAAGGAAGUUGCUUUACUUUUAGGCAUGUUGUGCCAGCUUCUGCCCAUGCAGCCUGUGCCAGAAUCUUCUGAUGGAUUAUUGACGGUGGAGCAGGUAAAAGAAAUAGGAGAUUACUUUAAACAACACCUUUUGCAGUCCAGGCACAGAGGAGCAUUUGAAUUGGCUUAUACUGGUUUUGUGAAACUCACUGAAGUACUAAACAGGUGCCCAAAUGUGAGUCUGCAAAAGCUGCCAGAACAGUGGCUAUGGAGUGUUUUAGAGGAAAUUAAAUGCAGUGAUCCUUCAUCUAAACUCUGUGCUACAAGGCGCAGUGCUGGAAUUCCUUUCUACAUACAGGCACUGUUGGCAUCUGAACCAAAGAAAGGCAGAAUGGAUUUGUUGAAAAUAACAAUGAAAGAGUUAAUCUCUUUGGCUGGGCCUACAGAUGACAUACAGAGUACAGUCCCCCAGGUUCAUGCUUUAAAUAUCCUUAGAGCAUUGUUCAGAGAUACGCGCCUGGGAGAAAAUAUUAUUCCUUAUGUUGCUGAUGGAGCUAAGGCUGCAAUUCUGGGUUUUACAUCACCGGUCUGGGCAGUGCGAAAUUCAUCCACACUUCUCUUUAGUGCCUUGAUCACAAGAAUUUUUGGAGUUAAAAGGGCAAAGGAUGAACAUUCCAAAACAAAUAGAAUGACAGGGAGAGAGUUUUUCUCUCGUUUCCCAGAACUCUAUCCUUUUCUUCUCAAACAGUUGGAAACUGUAGCCAAUACAGUAGACAGUGAUAUGGGAGAACCAAAUCGUCAUCCAAGCAUGUUUCUCUUACUUUUGGUGUUGGAGAGACUCUACGCUUCCCCGAUGGAUGGUACUUCUUCUGCUCUCAGCAUGGGACCUUUUGUUCCCUUCAUUAUGAGGUGUGGUCACUCACCUGUCUACCACUCCCGUGAAAUGGCAGCUCGUGCCUUGGUCCCAUUUGUUAUGAUAGAUCACAUUCCUAAUACCAUUCGAACUCUGUUGUCCACACUCCCCAGCUGCACUGACCAGUGUUUCCGGCAAAACCACAUUCAUGGGACACUUCUCCAGGUUUUUCAUUUGUUGCAAGCCUACUCAGACUCCAAACACGGAACGAAUUCAGACUUCCAGCACGAGCUGACUGACAUCACUGUUUGUACCAAAGCCAAACUCUGGCUGGCCAAGAGGCAAAAUCCAUGUUUGGUGACCAGAGCUGUAUAUAUUGAUAUUCUCUUCCUAUUGACUUGCUGCCUCAACAGAUCUGCAAAGGACAACCAGCCAGUUCUGGAGAGUCUUGGCUUCUGGGAGGAAGUCAGAGGGAUUAUCUCAGGAUCAGAGCUGAUAACGGGAUUCCCUUGGGCCUUCAAGGUGCCAGGCCUGCCCCAGUACCUCCAGAGCCUCACCAGACUAGCCAUUGCUGCAGUGUGGGCCGCGGCAGCCAAGAGUGGAGAGCGGGAGACGAAUGUCCCCAUCUCUUUCUCUCAGCUGUUAGAAUCUGCCUUCCCUGAAGUGCGCUCACUAACACUGGAAGCCCUCUUGGAAAAGUUCUUAGCAGCAGCCUCUGGACUUGGAGAGAAGGGCGUGCCACCCUUGCUGUGCAACAUGGGAGAGAAGUUCUUAUUGUUGGCCAUGAAGGAAAAUCACCCAGAAUGCUUCUGCAAGAUACUGAAAAUUCUCCACUGCAUGGACCCUGGUGAGUGGCUUCCCCAGACGGAGCACUGUGUCCAUCUGACCCCAAAGGAGUUCUUGAUCUGGACGAUGGAUAUUGCUUCCAAUGAAAGAUCUGAAAUUCAGAGUGUAGCUCUGAGACUUGCUUCCAAAGUCAUUUCCCACCACAUGCAGACAUGUGUGGAGAACAGGGAAUUGAUAGCUGCUGAGCUGAAGCAGUGGGUUCAGCUGGUCAUCUUGUCAUGUGAAGACCAUCUUCCUACAGAGUCUAGGCUGGCCGUCGUUGAAGUCCUCACCAGUACUACACCACUUUUCCUCACCAACCCCCAUCCUAUUCUUGAGUUGCAGGAUACACUUGCUCUCUGGAAGUGUGUCCUUACCCUUCUGCAGAGUGAGGAGCAAGCUGUUAGAGAUGCAGCCACGGAAACCGUGACAACUGCCAUGUCACAAGAAAAUACCUGCCAGUCAACAGAGUUUGCCUUCUGCCAGGUGGAUGCCUCCAUCGCUCUGGCCCUGGCCCUGGCCGUCCUGUGUGAUCUGCUCCAGCAGUGGGACCAGUUGGCCCCUGGACUGCCCAUCCUGCUGGGAUGGCUGUUGGGAGAGAGUGAUGACCUCGUGGCCUGUGUGGAGAGCAUGCAUCAGGUGGAAGAAGACUACCUGUUUGAAAAAGCAGAAGUCAACUUUUGGGCCGAGACCCUGAUCUUUGUGAAAUACCUCUGCAAGCACCUCUUCUGUCUCCUCUCAAAGUCCGGCUGGCGUCCCCCAAGCCCUGAGAUGCUCUGUCACCUUCAAAGGAUGGUGUCAGAGCAGUGCCACCUCCUGUCUCAGUUCUUCAGAGAGCUUCCACCAGCUGCUGAGUUUGUGAAGACAGUGGAGUUCACAAGACUACGCAUUCAAGAGGAAAGGACUUUGGCUUGCUUGAGGCUGCUGGCCUUUUUGGAAGGAAAGGAAGGGGAAGACACCCUAGUUCUCAGUGUUUGGGACUCUUAUGCAGAAUCGAGGCAGUUAACUCUUCCAAGAACAGAAGCGGCAUGUUGAAGAAAAUCUGGGGGAUUGGGAUGGGGGUAUGUGUGGAUUUUUCCUCCACUAAAUCUGCAGGAAACAUGUUGAACAUAAAUUCAAAAAUUUUAUCCCA